AUUCCUGAAGCUGACAGCAUUCGGGCCGAGAUGUCUCGCUCCGUGGCCUUAGCUGUGCUCGCGCUACUCUCUCUUUCUGGCCUGGAGGCUAUCCAGCGUACUCCAAAGAUUCAGGUUUACUCACGUCAUCCAGCAGAGAAUGGAAAGUCAAAUUUCCUGAAUUGCUAUGUGUCUGGGUUUCAUCCAUCCGACAUUGAAGUUGACUUACUGAAGAAUGGAGAGAGAAUUGAAAAAGUGGAGCAUUCAGACUUGUCUUUCAGCAAGGACUGGUCUUUCUAUCUCUUGUACUACACUGAAUUCACCCCCACUGAAAAAGAUGAGUAUGCCUGCCGUGUGAACCAUGUGACUUUGUCACAGCCCAAGAUAGUUAAGUGGGGUAAGUCUUACAUUCUUUUGUAAGCUGCUGAAAGUUGUGUAUGAGUAGUCAUAUCAUAAAGCUGCUUUGAUAUAAAAAAGGUCUAUGGCCAUACUACCCUGAAUGAGUCCCAUCCCAUCUGAUAUAAACAAUCUGCAUAUUGGGAUUGUCAGGGAAUGUUCUUAAAGAUCAGAUUAGUGGCACCUGCUGAGAUACUGAUGCACAGCAUGGUUUCUGAACCAGUAGUUUCCCUGCAGUUGAGCAGGGAGCAGCAGCAGCACUUGCACAAAUACAUAUACACUCUUAACACUUCUUACCUACUGGCUUCCUCUAGCUUUUGUGGCAGCUUCAGGUAUAUUUAGCACUGAACGAACAUCUCAAGAAGGUAUAGGCCUUUGUUUGUAAGUCCUGCUGUCCUAGCAUCCUAUAAUCCUGGACUUCUCCAGUACUUUCUGGCUGGAUUGGUAUCUGAGGCUAGUAGGAAGGGCUUGUUCCUGCUGGGUAGCUCUAAACAAUGUAUUCAUGGGUAGGAACAGCAGCCUAUUCUGCCAGCCUUAUUUCUAACCAUUUUAGACAUUUGUUAGUACAUGGUAUUUUAAAAGUAAAACUUAAUGUCUUCCUU